ACCUCUCAAGCAGCCAGCGCCUGCCUGAAUCUGUUCUGCCCCCUCCCCACCCAUUUCACCACCACCAUGACACCGGGCACCCAGUCUCCUUUCUUCCUGCUGCUGCUCCUCACAGUGCUUACAGCUACCACAGCCCCUAAACCCGCAACAGUUGUUACGGGUUCUGGUCAUGCAAGCUCUACCCCAGGUGGAGAAAAGGAGACUUCGGCUACCCAGAGAAGUUCAGUGCCCAGCUCUACUGAGAAGAAUGCUGUGAGUAUGACCAGCAGCGUACUCUCCAGCCACAGCCCCGGUUCAGGCUCCUCCACCACUCAGGGACAGGAUGUCACUCUGGCCCCGGCCACGGAACCAGCUUCAGGUUCAGCUGCCACCUGGGGACAGGAUGUCACCUCGGUCCCAGUCACCAGGCCAGCCCUGGGCUCCACCACCCCGCCAGCCCACGAUGUCACCUCAGCCCCGGACAACAAGCCAGCCCCGGGCUCCACCGCCCCCCCAGCCCACGGUGUCACCUCGGCCCCGGACACCAGGCCGGCCCCGGGCUCCACCGCCCCCCAAGCCCACGGUGUCACCUCGGCCCCGGACACCAGGCCGGCCCCGGGCUCCACCGCCCCCCCAGCCCACGGUGUCACCUCGGCCCCGGACACCAGGCCCGCCCCGGGCUCCACCGCCCCCCCAGCCCACGGUGUCACCUCGGCCCCGGACACCAGGUCCGCCCCGGGCUCCACCGCGCCCGCAGCCCACGGUGUCACCUCGGCCCCGGACACCAGGUCGGUCCCGGGCUCCACCGCCCCCCAAGCCCACGGUGUCACCUCGGCCCCGGACACCAGGCCGGCCCCGGGCUCCACCGCCCCCCCAGCCCACGGUGUCACCUCGGCCCCGGACACCAGGCCGGCCCCGGGCUCCACCGCCCCCCAAGCCCACGGUGUCACCUCGGCCCCGGACACCAGGCCGGCCCCGGGCUCCACCGCCCCCCCAGCCCACGGUGUCACCUCGGCCCCGGACACCAGGCCCGCCCCGGGCUCCACCGCCCCCCCAGCCCACGGUGUCACCUCGGCCCCGGACACCAGGCCCGCCCCGGGCUCCACCGCGCCCGCAGCCCACGGUGUCACCUCGGCCCCGGACACCAGGCCGGCCCCGGGCUCCACCGCCCCCCAAGCCCACGGUGUCACCUCGGCCCCGGACACCAGGCCGGCCCCGGGCUCCACCGCCCCCCCAGCCCACGGUGUCACCUCGGCCCCGGACACCAGGCCGGCCCCGGGCUCCACCGCCCCCCAAGCCCACGGUGUCACCUCGGCCCCGGACACCAGGCCGGCCCCGGGCUCCACCGCCCCCCCAGCCCACGGUGUCACCUCGGCCCCGGACACCAGGCCGGCCCCGGGCUCCACCGCCCCCCCAGCCCACGGUGUCACCUCGGCCCCGGACACCAGGCCGGCCCCGGGCUCCCCCCCCCCCCCAGCCCACGGUGUCACCUCGGCCCCGGAGAGCAGGCCGGCCCCGGGCUCCACCGCGCCCGCAGCCCACGGUGUCACCUCGGCCCCGGAGAGCAGGCCGGCCCCGGGCUCCACCGCGCCCGCAGCCCACGGUGUCACCUCGGCCCCGGAGAGCAGGCCGGCCCCGGGCUCCACCGCCCCCCCAGCCCACGGUGUCACCUCGGCCCCGGACACCAGGCCGGCCCCGGGCUCCACCGCCCCCCCAACCCACGGUGUCACCUCGGCCCCGGACACCAGUCCCGCCCCGGGCUCCACCGCCCCCCCAGCCCACGGUGUCACCUCGGCCCCGGACACAAGGCCCGCCCCGGGCUACACCGCGCCCGCAGCCCACGGUGUCACCUCGGCCCCGGACACCAGGCCGGCCCCGGGCUCCACCGCCCCCCAAGCCCACGGUGUCACCUCGGCCCCGGACACCAGGCCGGCCCCGGGCUCCACCGCCCCCCCAGCCCACGGUGUCACCUCGGCCCCGGACACCAGGCCGGCCCCGGGCUCCACCGCCCCCCCAGCCCACGGUGUCACCUCGGCCCCGGACACCAGGCCGGCCCCGGGCUCCACCGCCCCCCCAGCCCACGGUGUCACCUCGGCCCCGGAGAGCAGGCCGGCCCCGGGCUCCACCGCGAGAGCAGCCCACGGUGUCACCUCGGCCCCGGAGAGCAGGCCGGCCCCGGGCUCCACCGCCCCCCCAGCCCACGGUGUCACCUCGGCCCCGGACACCAGGCCGGCCCCGGGCUCCACCGCCCCCCCAGCCCACGGUGUCACCUCGGCCCCGGACACCAGGCCGGCCCCGGGCUCCACCGCCCCCCCAGCCCACGGUGUCACCUCGGCCCCGGACACCAGGCCGGCCCCGGGCUCCACCGCCCCCCCAGCCCACGGUGUCACCUCGGCCCCGGACACCAGGCCGGCCCCGGGCUCCACCGCCCCCCCAGCCCACGGUGUCACCUCGGCCCCGGACACCAGGCCGGCCCCGGGCUCCACCGCCCCCCCAGUCCACGGUGUCACCUCGGCCCCGGACACCAGGCCGGCACCGGGCUCCACCGCCCCCCCAGCCCACGGUGUCACCUCGGCCCCGGACACCAGGCCGGCCCCGGGCUCCACCGCCCCCCCAGCCCACGGUGUCACCUCGGCCCCGGACACCAGGCCGGCCCCGGGCUCCACCGCACCCCCAGCCCACGGUGUCACCUCGGCCCCGGACACCAGGCGGGCCCCGGGCUCCACCCCGGCCCCGGGCUCCACCGCCCCCCCAGCCCACGGUGUCACCUCGGCCCCGGACACCAGGCCGGCCCCGGGCUCCACCGCCCCCCCAGCCCAUGGUGUCACCUCGGCCCCGGACAACAGGCCCGCCUUGGGCUCCACCGCCCCUCCAGUCCACAAUGUCACCUCGGCCUCAGGCUCUGCAUCAGGCUCAGCUUCUACUCUGGUGCACAACGGCACCUCUGCCAGGGCUACCACAACCCCAGCCAGCAAGAGCACUCCAUUCUCAAUUCCCAGCCACCACUCUGAUACUCCUACCACCCUUGCCAGCCAUAGCACCAAGACUGAUGCCAGUAGCACUCACCAUAGCACGGUACCUCCUCUCACCUCCUCCAAUCACAGCACUUCUCCCCAGUUGUCUACUGGGGUCUCUUUCUUUUUCCUGUCUUUUCACAUUUCAAACCUCCAGUUUAAUUCCUCUCUGGAAGAUCCCAGCACCGACUACUACCAAGAGCUGCAGAGAGACAUUUCUGAAAUGUUUUUGCAGAUUUAUAAACAAGGGGGUUUUCUGGGCCUCUCCAAUAUUAAGUUCAGGCCAGGAUCUGUGGUGGUACAAUUGACUCUGGCCUUCCGAGAAGGUACCAUCAAUGUCCACGACGUGGAGACACAGUUCAAUCAGUAUAAAACGGAAGCAGCCUCUCGAUAUAACCUGACGAUCUCAGACGUCAGCGUGAGUGAUGUGCCAUUUCCUUUCUCUGCCCAGUCUGGGGCUGGGGUGCCAGGCUGGGGCAUCGCGCUGCUGGUGCUGGUCUGUGUUCUGGUUGCGCUGGCCAUUGUCUAUCUCAUUGCCUUGGCUGUCUGUCAGUGCCGCCGAAAGAACUACGGGCAGCUGGACAUCUUUCCAGCCCGGGAUACCUACCAUCCUAUGAGCGAGUACCCCACCUACCACACCCAUGGGCGCUAUGUGCCCCCUAGCAGUACCGAUCGUAGCCCCUAUGAGAAGGUUUCUGCAGGUAAUGGUGGCAGCAGCCUCUCUUACACAAACCCAGCAGUGGCAGCCACUUCUGCCAACUUGUAGGGGCACGUCGCCCGCUGAGCUGAGUGGCCAGCCAGUGCCAUUCCACUCCACUCAGGUUCUUCAGGGCCAGAGCCCCUGCACCCUGUUUGGGCUGGUGAGCUGGGAGUUCAGGUGGGCUGCUCACAGCCUCCUUCAGAGGCCCCACCAAUUUCUCGGACACUUCUCAGUGUGUGGAAGCUCAUGUGGGCCCCUGAGGGCUCAUGCCUGGGAAGUGUUGUGGUGGGGGCUCCCAGGAGGACUGGCCCAGAGAGCCCUGAGAUAGCGGGGAUCCUGAACUGGACUGAAUAAAACGUGGUCUCCCACUGCGCCAA